AGGAGCCGCCGCCAGUGGAGGCGGAGGAGGUAGAGGAGGCGGAGACGGCGGAGAAGGCGGAGAGGAAGGUGGAGGCGGAGGCGAAGGUGGAGGGGAAGGCGGAGGCGGCGGGGAAGGCGGAGGCGGCGGGGAAGGUGGACGCCACCGAGAAGGUGGAGACGGCGGGGAAGGUGGACGCCGCUGGGAAGGUGGAGACGGCGGAGGGUCCGGGCCGCCGGGCUGAGCUCAAGCUGGAGCCCGAACCCGAGCCGGUCCGGGAGGCGGAGCAGGAGCCGAAGCAGGAGCUGGAGGAUGAGAACCCAGCGCGGAGCGGCGGUGGCGGCAACAGCGACGAGGUUCCUCCCCCCACCCUUCCCUCCGAUCCACCGCGGCCCCCCGAUCCCUCUCCGCGUCGCAGUCGUGCGCCGCGCCGCCGACCCCGGCCCCGGCCCCAGACCCGGCUCCGUACCCCGCCGCAGCCUAGGCCCCGGCCCCCGCCCCGGCCCCGGCCCCGGCGCGGCCCUGGGGGCGGAUGCCUGGAUGUGGAUUUUGCCGUGGGGCCACCAGGCUGUUCUCACGUGAACAGCUUUAAGGUGGGAGAGAACUGGAGGCAGGAACUGCGGGUUAUCUACCAGUGCUUCGUGUGGUGUGGAACCCCAGAGACCAGGAAAAGCAAGGCAAAGUCCUGCAUCUGCCAUGUGUGUGGCACCCAUCUGAACAGACUCCACUCUUGCCUUUCCUGUGUCUUCUUUGGCUGCUUCACGGAGAAACACAUUCACGAGCACGCAGAGACGAAACAACACAACUUAGCAGUAGACCUGUAUUACGGAGGUAUAUACUGCUUUAUGUGUAAGGACUAUGUAUAUGACAAAGACAUUGAGCAAAUUGCCAAAGAAGAGCAAGGAGAAGCUUUGAAAUUACAAGCCUCCACCUCAACAGAGGUUUCUCACCAGCAGUGUUCAGUGCCAGGCCUUGGUGAGAAAUUCCCAACCUGGGAAACAACCAAACCAGAAUUAGAACUGCUGGGGCACAACCCGAGGAGAAGAAGAAUCACCUCCAGCUUUACGAUCGGUUUAAGAGGACUCAUCAAUCUUGGCAACACGUGCUUUAUGAACUGCAUUGUCCAGGCCCUCACCCACACGCCGAUACUGAGAGAUUUCUUUCUCUCUGACAGGCACCGAUGUGAGAUGCCGAGUCCCGAGUUGUGUCUGGUCUGUGAGAUGUCGUCGCUGUUUCGGGAGUUGUAUUCUGGAAACCCGUCUCCUCAUGUGCCCUAUAAGUUACUGCACCUGGUGUGGAUACAUGCCCGCCAUUUAGCAGGGUACAGGCAACAGGAUGCCCACGAGUUCCUCAUUGCAGCGUUAGAUGUCCUGCACAGGCACUGCAAAGGUGAUGAUGUCGGGAAGGCGGCCAACAAUCCCAACCACUGUAACUGCAUCAUAGACCAAAUCUUCACAGGUGGCCUGCAGUCUGAUGUCACCUGUCAAGCCUGCCAUGGCGUCUCCACCACGAUAGACCCAUGCUGGGACAUUAGUUUGGACUUGCCUGGCUCUUGCACCUCCUUCUGGCCCAUGAGCCCAGGGAGGGAGAGCAGUGUGAACGGGGAAAGCCACAUACCAGGAAUCACCACCCUCACGGACUGCUUGCGGAGGUUUACGAGGCCAGAGCACUUAGGAAGCAGUGCCAAAAUCAAAUGUGGUAGUUGCCAAAGCUACCAGGAAUCUACCAAACAGCUCACAAUGAAUAAAUUACCUGUCGUUGCCUGUUUUCAUUUCAAACGGUUUGAACAUUCAGCGAAACAGAGGCGCAAGAUCACUACAUACAUUUCCUUUCCUCUGGAGCUGGAUAUGACGCCGUUUAUGGCCUCAAGUAAAGAGAGCAGAAUGAAUGGACAAUUGCAGCUGCCAACCAAUAGUGGAAACAACGAAAAUAAGUAUUCCUUGUUUGCUGUGGUUAAUCACCAAGGAACCUUGGAGAGUGGCCACUAUACCAGCUUCAUCCGGCACCACAAGGACCAGUGGUUCAAGUGUGAUGAUGCCGUCAUCACUAAGGCCAGUAUUAAGGACGUACUGGACAGUGAAGGGUAUUUACUGUUCUAUCACAAACAGGUGCUAGAACAUGAGUCAGAAAAAGUGAAAGAAAUGAACACACAAGCCUACUGAAGUGACACACAGACCUACCUGCAAUGGAAGAUGACGACACCAAUACUACAACUGGCAUCGAGAUCUAAAGGACCUACUUGACCAUGGCCCAUGGGCCUGACAGAGUAAGAAUUGAACAGUACCCAGUGUCCAAAAGGUCCUGAUUGGAAGAGAAAUAGAAGGGGAGGGAGAAGAGGCUCUAGUCUAAGCAGUUGAUGAAAGGGAAAUUAAAUGGUAGAAACACUCUGGGUGAGGAAGGCAGGAGCAGGAAAAUGCUGACACUGGUACAUAUCCUAUAUUCCUCCAAAAGAUUGUGUGGGAAAGUGUGGGGGGGAGGGGGGUGGUGGGGGGGGAGUGUGCCCUUGUAACCGUAAAACAUCUUUCUCCAUGGGUGUUUCAGCUUCAAUUGACCAAUCACAUAACAGUUAUAUGUUUGGGGGGAAAAAGAAAAGUUUCUAAAAAAUGUAGCCCAUUACAUAUAUGGGUAUGAAAGCAGAAAAGUGGAGGAGGCAGGGAUAUCAUUGACAAACACCUUUGCCAGUUUCUUUGUAUUCGUGAUUUUUUGUGCUAUUAAAUGCAGUAUUAAAACAAGAAAAGCCCACCUGGGCUAGUGAAAGGAGAGGAAAUAAGGGGGCUUGUAAAAGGGGAGCCGUCGCUCCAAAAGUAGAGAAGACAAGAAAUGCUGUAAGAUAAGCAACCAACGCAGACAGGCCUCAGCUAAGAGUAUAGUGUGUGUGUGUUAAAAAAAAAAAAAAAAAAAGAAAAAAAAAAGCUGUAUGAUAUACUUGAGCAAAUCAAUGAACCUCUUUGCGAUUGUUUUAUCAUCUGUAAAAUGCAGAUAAUUCCUACCUUAAAGGGUUAUUGUUAAAGAUAAAAUGAUAUAAAAAUGUGUCAAAGUAUAAAGUAAAAGGCUUGGAACUUUGUAGGGACUCAGUAAACGUUUGUUGGAUCCAAA